CUGGGGGCGGCCGGCGGGUGUGGAGGGUUCAUUCAGGGAGCUGCGGGCGAGUCGGGUGGGCACGGGGGCCGCCCACAGGUGCACCGCGCGUCCUCAGCCGCUUCCCCUGCCCACCUUCUGCGACCCCUUCCCGCCCCCACCCUCCUGGGCCGUCUUGCAGGCCCGAGCUUGUGUCCGCCUCGCUGGGCAAGGUGUUUCGGGGACGACUCCUGCCGGCGUUUGCCCUCCGGGCUCGGUCCUUGCCUCUUCGCCGGUGGGCACCUGCUAGGAGAACUAUGCCAUUUUUGGGUCAGGACUGGAGAUCUCCUGGAUGGAGUUGGAUUAAGACAGAAGAUGGCUGGAAGAGAUGUGAAUCUUGUAGUCAGAAACUUGAAAGAGAGAAUAACCGUUGUAACAUCAGUCACAGCAUUAUCUUAAAUAGUGAAGAUGGAGAAAUAUUCAAUAAUGAAGAGCAUGAAUAUGCAUCGAAAAAAAGGAAAAAGGACCAUUUUAGAAAUGACACAAAUACUCAAAGUUUUUAUCGUGAAAAAUGGAUCUAUGUCCAUAAAGAAAGCACAAAGGAAAGGCAUGGCUAUUGCACCUUGGGAGAAGCCUUUAAUCGGUUAGACUUCUCAAGUGCAAUUCAAGAUAUCCGAAGGUUCAAUUAUGUGGUCAAACUGUUGCAGCUAAUUGCAAAAUCCCAGUUAACUUCAUUGAGUGGCGUGGCACAGAAGAAUUACUUCAACAUUUUGGAUAAAAUCGUUCAAAAGGUUCUUGAUGACCACCACAAUCCUCGCUUAAUCAAAGAUCUUCUGCAAGACCUAAGCUCUACCCUCUGCAUUCUUAUUAGAGGAGUAGGGAAGUCUGUAUUAGUGGGAAACAUCAAUAUUUGGAUUUGCCGAUUAGAAACUAUUCUCGCCUGGCAACAACAGCUACAGGAUCUUCAGAUGACUAAGCAAGUGAACAAUGGCCUCACCCUCAGUGACCUUCCUCUGCACAUGCUGAACAACAUCCUAUACCGGUUCUCAGACGGAUGGGACAUCAUCACCUUAGGCCAGGUGACCCCCACGUUGUAUAUGCUUAGUGAAGACAGACAGCUGUGGAAGAAGCUUUGUCAGUACCAUUUUGCUGAAAAGCAGUUUUGUAGACAUUUGAUCCUUUCAGAAAAAGGUCAUAUUGAAUGGAAGUUGAUGUACUUUGCACUUCAGAAACAUUACCCAGCGAAGGAGCAGUACGGAGACACACUGCAUUUCUGUCGGCACUGCAGCAUUCUCUUUUGGAAGGACUACCAUCUUGCUUUACUAUUCAAGGACUCAGGACACCCCUGCACGGCGGCCGACCCUGACAGCUGCUUCACGCCUGUGUCUCCGCAGCACUUCAUCGACCUCUUCAAGUUUUAAGGGCUGCCCCUGCCAUCCCUAUUGGAGAUUGUGAAUCCUGCUGUCUGUGCAGGGCUCAUAGUGAGUGUUCUGUGAGGUGGGUGGAGACUCCUCGGAAGCCCCUGCUUCCAGAAAGCCUGGGAAGAACUGCCCUUCUGCAAAGGGGGGACUGCAUGGUUGCAUUUUCAUCACUGAAAGUCAGAGGCCAAGGAAAUCAUUUCUACUUCUUUAAAAACUCCUUCUAAGCAUAUUAAAAUGUGAAAUUUUGCGUACUCUCUCUCUCUAUAUAUAUAGUUCAAAAAUACUUUAGGUGGUCAGCUCCACAUUCUUUGUUGACGUGACACUAACGGCCAAUAAUAUGCUUCUUAAUUAUCAAAUUAUAGUUUCCCAAUUGGGAAACUAAUUGGGGGUGGGUUACAAAACAUUUGAUCCUUGUAAAUACAUUGUACAGAAUAUUUAUUUUUUCUCAAAAUGCAUUUUAACUACUACAUUGGCUGUGCCCAAAUGAGUCCUCUUUGAAUAGAAAGUGAACCCAGGGCAAUGACAGCCAUUCUUGUCUUAGGGAUUAUGGAUCGGGGUAUGAAGUGUGCACACGCAGCCCAACAACGGGCAGUGGUCUCUGUGCUCCUAGGCAUCCAGCACAGGUUCUGGCAGGGCACCCCUGCUGGGGUUGGGGGCUGGUCUGUGCAUAAUCCUGGACUGUGAUGGGAACAGCCCAGUGCAGUCUAAACUUCAAUUGUGUUGAAACUACUUUAAUAGACAAAGUAAUAAAUCAUGUUUAUCUAUUGAUUUAAACUUCAUCAGUUUUGCAUCCUACUGAGAAAUGUUAGUGAUUUUGAUACUUAAAUCCUUAAAAGAUUGCUUCGUUUUUAAAAUAACGCAUGUCCAUUUUAGAAAAUUAGAAAAUCAGUCCCACCACCCAAAGAUUAUUGUGCAUGCUGAAAAGAGUAUGAAAAAUCCCCUCAGCAGGCAUAGGAUAGAAACGUAUUGUUGUAUAUUUCCAUUUUUGAAUAGGGUCAAGGAGCCCAAGCAAAUCAUUUCUACUUUUUCCUUUAAGCAUAAUAAUAAAAGUAUACUUUUAUGGCGUUAUAAAUAGGACUAAAAAAAGAUUCUGGAUUUUUCAGCCCCACUUCUGUGAACUGACACAAAUGGCCAAGAAUGCAUUUAUUUGUCAAAUUAUAGUUUCUCCUGAGGCGAUGCAAAUACCUGGGGCCUCUGCGAAUAUAUGUUAGUUUUUCAUAAGACCAUAAAUGUCCCGUAUACCACUGUUACUUCACAACGCCCCCCGUCCCGACCCUGCCUUUUUUUAGAAACGUAGAACCAUAUCCUAAAUGUUAUUUGGAAACUUGGCUUUUAUUAGCUCCACAGAAUCACCCAGAUGGAACAGGCUUUUUCAUCACAACAUAUUGGGGUUCCUGAGUGUCUCGCCGUUAGCAUCAAUAACUAUGAUAAGCAUCGUCACACAACAAUGUGGCCGUCUCCUUACAACCACUGGUAGUACAGCCAACAUCAUGAGUCAAACAUAUUUUAAGGCUUUUAAAUAUAUUUCUAGAUUGUUCAUGAAAAAAAAUUUUUUUGGAGUUUGUUUUUGAGACAGGGUCUUGCUCUGUCACCCAGGCUGGAGUGCAGGGGUAUGAUGUCGGCUUACUGCAACCUCUGUCCCCCAGGCUCAAGUGAUCCUCCCACCUCACCCUCCAGUGAUCCUCCCACCUCAGCCUCCCAAGCAGUCAGGACCACAGGCAUAUACCACCAUGCUCAGCUGUUUUUUUGUAUUUUUAGUAGAGAUGGGGUUUCACCAUGUUGCCCAGGCUGGUCUCAGGAGUUUGAGCUCAAGCAAUCCACCUGCCUCAGCUUCCCAAAGUGCUGGGAUUACAGGCAUGAGCCACCACGUCCAGCUGAGAAAAGAAAUUGUUCUAAUCUAGGAAAGGGAGUAAGUACAUUGAGUUUCCAUUAUCCCUGAAGCACAGGUAUUUCUUUUUCUGUUGGUGCUGUUUUAAUAAGUGAAGAAUUUGAUGUAUGAUAAAUUGUGAGCUUGAAUAUUUCCAUAUAUUUAUUAUCCAUUUGCUUUUCUUGUUUUUGGUAAAUUACUUAAUGUGGUAUUUGCCUGUUUUUUGGGGUGGAUGUCAGUCUUUUUUCAUGUUAGUUUCUUCUUAAAAGGAAACUAUCCUUUUGAAGUUGUGGUUCUUUCCCCUAAUUUGUCAUAUACUGUUACUGUCAUUUAAUUGUUAGAUGUUAUAACAGUUCUCAGCUGUGCUAUCAAAUCACAGAUGUGCAUUUAACUUGUAUAAAUUGAGCAGUACUUGCUUGGAAAACAUAACCAUAUUAAUAGUGUAGGAUUCCAGCUGUUCUGCUGGGCUGGCAUAUUUCCACAGGCCAUGGACACAGCUAGCCGCAUUGCCACUGCAUGGGUCACAGCCUCCUGCAGGUGCGUUCGAGGGACAAGCUGUGGGAGCUGGGCAGGUAAGCAGGGAUGGCUUACAUUGCUGGGGAGAGAUUGAAAGGUUAAUGGAGGGUAUAAGGACAGAAUAAAGACAAUUUUGAGGCACUGAUCAGUUAUUUACAGAAGAUCGGACAACACCAAACAGAGAUGAGAAGAGAAAUCAUAGAUCUCCACUUUGGAAUGGUAUUUUUGAAUACAGUUUCUAUCAGGGGGCCUUCCAAAAGUAGGGAUGCCACUCCUGUGAGAUUAAGUUACAUUCUGAUGCCUUCAUUACAAUGAAGUAGAUAAUUCAGGACCCCAGGAGCCUAAAGCCAGGUAGUAAGUUUCACUUGCCCAUCGCUCCUGUGAAAGGCAAUGCCAGACACUCUCAAGAUAGAAUCUCCAGUCAUUCUCGGACCUGUUCUCAGUCUGCGCUGCUCACUCAGGGCUGGUGUCUCUUGACACCCAGUUACAACUUCCUUUUGCCUAUUUUGAGUCAAAAAGUCACAUUCCUCACCUAAUUUAUGAAUACACACAAAUUGGAAAGCCAUGCAGUAGCCUCUCAGGAGCAGACCGAUUUGUAGCUGUCGUGGUUUACUGCAUGACGUACAGGCUCUCUGUAUGCACUGUGUGUGCGUACUGUACAGGGCUGUACACAGCAAACUGUGUCUACUUUAUGGAAAAAAUUUAACCAUCUGUGAACAGUUUUUUGCCUUAAGUGCUGCUUUUAGAACCAAACUGUCAUAUAAGAUUUAUCAGCUCUUUUAACACCUUUGUAGAUUCCUGAUGCUGUGUACAAAAUCAUGUCAUCUAUGAAUAGACAGUUUCACUUCUUCCUCUCAGUCUAGAUGUCCUUUAUUCUUUCUUACCCCGUUUCGCUGGCUAGAAUCUCUAGUACAAUGUUGAAUAGCAGUGCGAGAGUGAACAUCCUUGUCUUGUUCCUCAUCUUAGGGGAAAGCUUUCAGUCUCACCAUUAACUAUGAUGUUAACCCUGGGUUUUCCAUACAUACCCUCUAUUAGGUUGGGGAGGUUCCCUUCUAUUCCUAGUUUGUUUUUAUCGUGAAAGGGUGUGGAUUUUGUCAAAUGCUUUUUCUGCAUCUCUUAAGAUAAUGUAGUUUUUGGCCUUCAUAAGAUCAUGUGCUGUUAUUACAUUGACUGAUUUCUAUAUCUUGAACCAACCUUGCAUUCUUGGGUCAAAGCCCACUAAGUCAUGGUUUAUGAUACCUUUUAUACAUAGCUGUUAGAUUUGGUGUGCUGGAACAGCCAGCCCUCUGUAUCCACGGGGGAUUGGUUCCAAGACCCCCACCCCCACCCCACCUGCCACCCACCACCUUGUGAUCUCUUGGGUUUUGGUGUCCAUCUCAUAGGAUAAGCUUAGAAAGUGUUCCCUCUUCUGUGUUUUGGAAGUGUUUGUGGUGGUUUCUUGUUAAUUCUUCUUUAAAUGUUUGAGAGAACUCCAUAUAAGAUUUGAAGUCACUGAGAAGCUUCAAUUAUCCUUUAAGAGGAUAAGACCAUUUUCUCCAGAGAUGCCUUUUAAUGGUUUUUCUUUUCAUUGCGAAGGCCUAACUUAGUAGAUAAGUGGACUGUGAAACCUAGUCUGUUCUGCUUAUCUUCAGAAUUAUCAAAAGGAAGGGGUGCUGCCCUCUGAGAAAAGUCAGAAGCAAGCCUGCCUUAUGAAACUCGACUUUUUAAUCUCCCUCUCUUCAUUAUGAUGUGUGCACGUGAUGGACACCACUCACCUCCCUUUAGUCCCUAUCAAAUGCUACCCAAUGGCAAAGCCAAGGGAUUAGCAACAGGUAGGAGGAAAAAGAAGGACCUGCAUACAUGACUAACCAGCACCAGCCAUUGGGGCCCUCUAUGGCUGACACCAGCAUCCACCCUGCACUCAUAUGUAUCUCAACAGAAUUGCUGCUUCUGUCUUCACUCAAGCCCCACUCCUUAUCCCUUCCUGUUGUUUCUGCAUAGAGGAGGCAGACCCUCAACUUUGGAAAGCAGUGUCCCCCCGCGUCCCAUGGGCUAAAUGCCACUGAGCCGGUAGGAGCUGCUCAGGUGUAGCCUCUGCCUUCAGAAUUUCAGCAGGAACUGCAUCAUUGUGUGCCUAAAAAGCCCUGGCUCACAGCAUGAGACAGUGUGUUCUAGGUGGUAACGUGGCACCUGCACAUGCACCCCCAGCAGUCCUCUCUAAACUCAGGCAGUGUAUGGCUGCUGCCAUUCUCGCCCUCAGCAUCUGUGAGAUGAAGGAGUUGCUCCCCAGGGCACCUGCCCCAAUACAGGCCACGUGGAUCUGCCAUUGCUUUUCACGUGAAUGCCUAGGAGAGGCUGUUAACCCUCCUAGUUGUCCUUUUUGUACUUGGUCCUCUUCCUUCCAAUCCUCACUGGCUCAAAUCCACAGAGUGACAAAGAACAGAGAUGCCCAGAGCACCAGCUGGAGGGGCAAGCAGGAGAAGGCACUGCUGGUGCCACAGGGGUCCUGGGCUGGCUCUUGGACCAUAACCAGCGUUCACUGAGGAUGCGGUUUCUUUGAAAUGCUCUUGUUCUUCCUAAGUAAGGGAGAGCAAAAAAAAUGAGGACAUCUGUGUCAAAUAGAAGAGACACCUCAACUGUCUCGUUUUUGCAUGGAAAUUUCAUUUUUAUUUGAUAAUCAUUUGAGAAACUUGCACAGAUGAAGGCAAGUUGGUUUUUAUUAUCUAACCUAUGUAGUCAAUUCUAAUGUCAUUUAAAAGAAUUUGACAUGUUAAAAUACACGUGAAAUUUACCAUCUUACCUAUUUUAAGUGUGCAAUUUAGUGGCAUUAAAUACAUUCAUACUGUGCAACCUUCUCUACCACGUAUCCACAAGUUCAACUUUACAAGAUGAACUUUUGUCAUCUUGUAAAACUGAAGCUCUGUACCCAUUAAGCACCAACUCCCUAUUCCCCAUCCACCAGCCCCUGGCAGCCUCUGUUCUCCUUUGUCUCUUUUAAUUUGACUUCUGUAGGGACCUCGUAUGAGUGGAACCAGAAGGGAUUUGUCCUUUUGUGACUGGCUUAUUUCACUUAGCGUAAUGUCCUCAAGGUUUAUUCAAGUUGUAGGAUAUGUCAAGAUUUCUUUUUAAGGCUGAUUCUAUGGAUGGACCACAUUUUGUUUGUGUACUCAUCUGUUGAGGACACUUGAGUUGCUUCCACCUUUUAGCUAUUGUGAAUAUUGCUGCCGUAAACAUGGGUGUGCAAAUAUCUGAGUCUCUGCUUUCAAUCAUAUGGCAAUCCUAUGUUUAAUUUCUUAGGGCACUGCCAUAAGUGUUUUACACGGUGGCUGCACCAUUUUACAUUCCCACUGAAGGUUCCAGUUUUGCCACAUCCUUGCCAACACCUGUUUUUAAUAAUUGCCAUCCUAAUGAGUGUGAAGUGGUAUCCUGCUGAGAUUUUGAUUUGCAUUUCCGUAAUGACUGGUGAUGCUGAGUAUCUGUUUGUUGGCCGUUUAUAUGUCGUCUUUGGAGAAAUGUCUAUUUGGGCUCUUUGUCCAUUUUUCAAUCAGGUGUGUGUUUUUAUAUGUUCUGGGUAUUCACCCUUUUCAGAUAUAUCAUUUUAAAAUACUUUGUCCCAUUCCGUGGAUUGCCUUUCACUCUGUUUUGUUCUUUGAUGUACAGAAGUUGUUUCUUUCUUUUAGUUACCUGUGUGUGCCUCUGGUGUCAUAUCUAAGAAAUCACUGCCUCACCCUUUUCAGAUAUAUCAUUUUAAAAUACUUUGUCCCAUUCCGUGGAUUGCCUUUCACUCUGUUUUGUUCUUUGAUGUACAGAAGUUGUUUCUUUCUUUUAGUUACCUGUGUGUGCCUCUGGUGUCAUAUCUAAGAAAUCACUGCCAAAUCCAAUGUUGUUAAAAGUUUCCCUUAUGUUUCUCCUAAAUGUUUUAGUUUUAGCUCUUAGUUUAGGCCUUUGAUCUAUUUUAAUUUUUAUAUAUGGUGUGAGGUAGAUCUAGCUUCAUGUGGAUGUCCACUUGUCUAGCACCAUUUGUUGAAAAGACUGUCCUUUCUCCCUUGAAUGGUCUUGGCACCAUCAAAAAUCAUUUGACCCAUAUGUGCAAGGGUUUAUUUGGGGAUUUGCUAUUCUGUUCCAUUGGUCUACAUGACUGUCUUUGUUUCAAUACAACACCAUUUUGAUUAUUGUAGCUUUGUCGUAAGUUAUGAAAUAAGGAAGUGAGAGACCUCCUACUUGGUUCCCUUUCAAGAUGAUUUUGGCUGUGUGAGGUCUCUUGAGAUUCCAUAUGAGUUUCAGGAUGGAAAAAAAAAAGCCACUGGGAUAUUCUGAUAGAGAUUGCAUGAAAUCUAUAGAUUGCUUUGGACUAUGGACAUCUUAAGGUAUCCAAUCCAUAAACACGGGAUUGCUUUCUAUUUAUUUGUGUUGACCUUACUUUCUUUAAGCAGUGUUUUAUGGUUUUCAAGUACAAGUCUUUUGCUUCCUUAAGUUUAUUCCUAAAUAUUUCAGUUUUUUUGUUACUAUUAUAAUGGAAUUUUCUUAAAUUUCCUUUUGAGAUUGCUUGUUAUUGUAUAGAAAUAUCAUGGAUUUGUUGUGUUGAUUUUGUAAACUGCAGUGUUACUGAAAUUUUUUUUUGUAUAUGUAUGGACACUAGGAUUUUCUACAUAUAAGAUCAUGUCAUCUGCAAACAGAUAAUUUUGCUUCUUCCUUUCCAGUCUGGAUGCCUUUUAUUUCUUUUUCUUGCCUAACUGCUCUAAGACUCCAGUACUGUGUUAAACAGAAGUGGUGAGACAGGGUAUUUCUGUGUUGUUCUUGAUCUUAAAGUCCUUUCAGUCUUAUUGAAUAUGAUGUUUACAGUGGGAUGUUCAUAUGGCCUCUAUUUUAGGUUGUUUCCUUCUAUUCCCAAUUGUUGAGUUUUUAUCAUGAAAGGGCAUGACAUUGUCUCAAAUGCUUUUUCUCCAUCAAUGGAGAUCACAUUUUUUUCCUUCAUUCUAUUAAUGUAAUAGACAUUACAUUUAUUGACUUGAGCAUGUUGAAACAUCUUUGCAUACCAGCUGUAAAUCUUACUUGGCCAUGAUGUGUAAUCCUUUCAAUGUCCCACUGAAUCCUGUUGGCCAGUAUUUUGUUGAAUAUUGAUUUAAAAAAAUCUUGAUCAGGAAUACUGAUGUGUGGUGUUUUUUUCUUAUAGUGUCUUUGUCUGGUUUUGGUAUCAGAAUAAUGAUGGCCUCAUAGAAUGCAUUUGGAAGUGUCCUUUCCUCUUCAGUUUUUUGGAAGAGUUUGAGGAGAAUUGAUUUAAUUCUUCAGAUGUUUGCCAGAAUUCCCAUAUGACCCUGGGCUUUUCUUUCUUGGGAGGCUUUUCUUUACUACUUCAUGCUCUUGACUAGCAUAGGUCUGUUCAGAUUUUCCAUUUCUUCAUGAUUCAAUCUUGAUAGGCUGUGUGUUUCUAAGAAUUUGUCCAGUUCAUCUAGGUUAUCCAAUUCUUUGAUAUGUAAUUGCUCAUAGUACUCUUAAUCCUUUUUAUUUCUGUAAAAUCAGUUGUAAUGUCUCCUCCUGGUUUUUAGUUGUUUUUCUUAGUCACUCUUAGCUAUCAACAAACUCUUGGUUUCAUUUAUUUUUCUCUAUUGCUUUUCUGUUCUCUAUUUUGUCUCUGCUCUAAUCUUUAUUAUUAUUAUAAUCAUCUCCAUUCUGCUGGCUUUGGGUUGAUUGCUCUUCUUUUUCUAGUUCUUUCAGAUGUAAAUUUAGGGUUGACUUGAGAUCUUAAUUUGUUUAAUAGGUGUAUUUACAGUUACAAAUUUCCCUCCUACCACUGCUUUGACUGUACCUGUUUUUUUGUAUAUUACAUUUUUCAUUUACCACAAGAUAUUUUCUAAUUUCCCUUGUGAGUUCCCCAUUAAUCUGCUGGUUGAGAGCGUUGUUUAAUUUUCACAUAAUUGUGUACUUUUCAGUUUUUUGUCUGUUACUGAUUUCUAGUUUCAUCCCACUGUGGCCAGAAAAGAUAUUUUAUUUCCUCAGUCUUUUGAAAUUUGUUGACUUGUUUAGUCAUCUAACAUACUGUCUAUCCUAGAGAAAGGUCCAUUUGCACUUGAGAAAAACGUGUGUACUGCUGUUGUGUCUGUUAGGUCCAGCUGGUAUGAUGCUGUUCAAGUUCUGUCUUGCGACUGAUCUUCUGUCUGGUUGUCCUAUCCGUUACUGAAAGUGGGCUACUGCAGUCUCCUACUCUUACUGUAGAACUAUCCAUUUCUUCCUUUGAUUCUGUCAAUGUUUGUUUCAUAUAUUUUGGGCUCUGAUGUUUGGUGCAUAUAUAUUACAUCUUGGUGAAUUUUCAAACUUUUUAAAUUUCAACAUGAAGAUGAAAUUAUAGGAUGUCUGGGAUUUCCUUUGAAUCCGUGGGGCUGGGAGUAACUAUAAAUGAAACAAGAUUGGCCGGGAAUUUGAGGCUGCAAGGAUAGGUACACACAGGGGAGUGAAGCAGGGCUUGGAGCAGAUGGUAAAGAUUGUUGGCUUUUCCAGCCAUGGGGCUCUCUUGCCACUUGGCAGUAGUGGCAUGAAGCCGCCACCAGGGGGCCACGCACCAGUGCAUGUGGCUGUGUUCCAAACUUUUUGGACAAUAAAAUCUGAAUUUCACAUACUUUUCUUAUGUCAUUAGAUAUUACCCUUUUACAUCUUUUCACUAUUUAAAAAUGUAAAAAUCAUUCUUAACAUUUGGGCUGUGCAAAAACAGCUGGUGGGCCCAAUUUUGGCCUGUAUUUCACUUGCCAACCUGAUUUAUACUUUUGUAUCUAUUUGACAUUUUCCAUUAAAAGUUAUAUAACACUA